GUCACACCGACCUGCACCAUCUCUCGCCUGCCUGUGGGGUUUCUGUCAACUAGUCGUGGAGGGAAGGAGACUCUUUAAAGAAUAACAUCUUAUUGUGGCCAUGCCAGAACCCACUAAGAAAGAGGAAAAUGAAGUGCCAGCCCCAGCCCCACCCCCGGAAGAACCAAGUAAAGAGAAGGAGGCCGGAACUACACCAGCAAAAGAUGAAGAGGAAGUCUCCCCGCCUAGCGCCUUGCCUCCAGGUUUGGGUAGUCGGGCCCUGGAGAGAAAAGAUUCAGACUGGACCCUUGUCGAAACUCCUCCUGGGGAGGAACAAGCCAAGCAGAAUGCCAACUCCCAGCUGUCCAUCUUGUUCAUUGAAAAACCUCAAGGAGGAACAGUGAAAGUUGGUGAAGAUAUCACCUUCAUAGCCAAAGUCAAGGCUGAAGAUCUUCUGAGAAAACCCACUAUCAAAUGGUUCAAAGGAAAAUGGAUGGACCUGGCCAGCAAAGCCGGGAAGCACCUUCAGCUGAAGGAAACCUUUGAGAGGCACAGUCGGGUGUACACAUUUGAGAUGCAGAUCAUCAAGGCCAAAGAUAACUUUGCAGGAAAUUACAGAUGCGAGGUCACCUAUAAGGAUAAGUUUGACAGCUGUUCAUUUGAUCUUGAAGUGCACGAAUCUACUGGGACUACUCCAAACAUUGACAUCAGAUCUGCUUUCAAGAGAAGUGGAGAAGGUCAAGAGGAUGCAGGAGAACUUGACUUUAGUGGUCUCCUGAAACGUAGGGAGGUGAAGCAGCAGGAGGAAGAACCCCAGGUGGACGUAUGGGAGUUGCUGAAGAACGCGAAACCCAGUGAGUACGAGAAGAUCGCCUUCCAGUAUGGAAUCACCGACCUGCGCGGCAUGCUCAAGCGACUCAAGCGCAUGCGCAGAGAGGAGAAGAAGAGCGCAGCUUUUGCAAAAAUUCUUGAUCCUGCAUAUCAGGUUGACAAAGGAGGCAGAGUGAGGUUUGUUGUGGAGCUGGCAGAUCCAAAGUUGGAGGUGAAAUGGUAUAAAAAUGGUCAAGAAAUUCGACCCAGUACCAAAUACAUCUUUGAACACAAAGGAUGCCAGAGAAUCCUGUUUAUCAAUAACUGUCAGAUGACAGAUGAUUCAGAGUAUUAUGUGACAGCCGGUGAUGAGAAAUGUUCCACUGAGCUCUUCGUAAGAGAGCCUCCAAUUAUGGUGACCAAACAGCUGGAAGAUACAACUGCUUAUUGUGGGGAGAGAGUGGAAUUAGAAUGUGAGGUGUCUGAAGAUGAUGCCAAUGUAAAAUGGUUUAAGAAUGGUGAAGAGAUUAUCCCUGGUCCAAAAUCAAGAUACCGAAUUAGAGUUGAGGGUAAAAAACACAUCUUGAUCAUAGAGGGAGCAACAAAGGCUGAUGCUGCAGAAUAUUCAGUAAUGACAACAGGAGGACAAUCAUCUGCUAAACUUAGUGUUGACUUGAAACCUCUGAAGAUUUUGACACCUCUGACUGAUCAGACUGUAAAUCUUGGAAAAGAAAUCUGCCUGAAGUGUGAAAUCUCUGAAAACAUACCAGGAAAAUGGACUAAAAAUGGCCUACCUGUUCAGGAGAGUGACCGUCUAAAGGUGGUUCACAAGGGAAGGAUCCACAAGUUAGUGAUAGCCAAUGCCCUCACUGAAGAUGAAGGUGAUUAUGUAUUUGCACCUGAUGCCUACAAUGUUACUCUGCCUGCCAAAGUUCAUGUUAUUGAUCCUCCUAAGAUCAUCCUGGAUGGUCUUGAUGCUGACAACACAGUGACAGUGAUUGCAGGAAACAAGCUUCGUCUUGAGAUCCCCAUCAGCGGAGAACCACCUCCUAAAGCCAUGUGGAGCCGGGGAGAUAAGGCUAUUAUGGAAGGCAGUGGCCGGAUAAGAACAGAAUCUUACCCUGAUAGCAGCACUCUGGUCAUUGAUAUAGCUGAAAGAGAUGACUCUGGUGUUUACCACAUCAAUCUGAAAAACGAAGCUGGAGAGGCACAUGCAAGCAUCAAGGUUAAAGUUGUGGACUUCCCUGAUCCUCCAGUGGCACCGACUGUGACAGAGGUGGGAGAUGACUGGUGUAUCAUGAACUGGGAGCCUCCUGCCUACGACGGAGGCUCUCCAAUCCUAGGAUAUUUUAUUGAGAGGAAGAAGAAACAAAGCUCCAGGUGGAUGAGGCUGAAUUUUGAUCUCUGCAAAGAAACAACUUUUGAGCCCAAGAAGAUGAUUGAAGGUGUGGCCUAUGAGGUCCGCAUCUUUGCAGUCAAUGCCAUUGGCAUCUCCAAGCCCAGUAUGCCCUCCAGGCCUUUUGUUCCUUUGGCUGUAACAAGCCCUCCUACUCUUCUGACUGUGGACUCUGUCACUGACACGACUGUCACGAUGAGGUGGCGCCCCCCAGACCACAUUGGUGCAGCAGGUUUAGAUGGCUAUGUGCUAGAGUAUUGCUUUGAAGGAAGUACAUCAGCAAAACAGUCUGAUGAAAAUGGGGAGGCUGCCUAUGAUCUGCCAGCUGAGGACUGGAUAGUUGCAAACAAAGAUCUGAUUGACAAGACGAAGUUCACCAUCACAGGUCUGCCAACAGAUGCAAAGAUCUUUGUGCGUGUGAAGGCUGUUAAUGCAGCUGGUGCCAGCGAGCCCAAGUACUAUUCUCAGCCCAUUCUCGUGAAGGAAAUCAUAGAACCUCCAAAGAUUCGCAUUCCAAGACACCUGAAGCAAACCUAUAUCCGCAGAGUUGGAGAAGCUGUCAAUCUGGUUAUACCUUUCCAGGGAAAACCAAGACCAGAAUUAACUUGGAAGAAGGAUGGUGCAGAAAUUGAUAAGAAUCAAAUAAACAUUCGCAACUCUGAGACUGAUACAAUCAUAUUUAUUAGAAAAGCAGAGAGGAGCCACUCUGGGAAAUAUGAUCUGCAAGUCAAAGUGGACAAAUUCGUGGAGACCGCAUCAAUUGACAUCCAGAUCAUUGACCGUCCAGGUCCACCCCAAAUUGUGAAGAUUGAGGAUGUCUGGGGAGAAAAUGUCGCUCUCACAUGGACUCCACCAAAGGAUGAUGGAAAUGCUGCUAUCACAGGCUAUACCAUUCAGAAGGCUGACAAGAAGAGCAUGGAAUGGUUUACUGUCAUUGAGCAUUAUCAUCGAACCAGUGCCACCAUUACUGAAUUGGUCAUAGGGAAUGAAUAUUACUUCCGGGUCUUUUCUGAAAACAUGUGUGGCCUCAGUGAGGAUGCCACCAUGACUAAAGAGAGUGCAGUGAUCGCCAGGGAUGGUAAAAUCUACAAAAAUCCAGUGUAUGAAGACUUUGAUUUCUCAGAGGCACCCAUGUUUACUCAGCCUUUGGUUAACACCUAUGCCAUAGCUGGUUACAAUGCCACCCUAAACUGCAGUGUGAGAGGAAAUCCUAAGCCUAAAAUAACCUGGAUGAAAAACAAAGUUGCUAUUGUGGAUGAUCCAAGAUACAGGAUGUUCAGCAACCAGGGAGUCUGUACCCUGGAAAUUCGCAAGCCCAGCCCCUAUGAUGGAGGCACUUACUGCUGCAAAGCAGUCAAUGACCUUGGGACAGUGGAGAUUGAAUGCAAACUGGAGGUGAAAGUGAUAUAUCAAGGAGUAAAUACCCCUGGACAACCAGUCUUCCUGGAGGGGCAGCAACAGUCAUUGCACAAUAAGGAUUUUUGAAUGUAUAAUAUCAUCUAAGGUGGGCUCUCCUUCUGCAGACUCCUCUUGCAAGGCGUACCUCCAAACAUAAUUGAUUCGUAUCUGCGAGACUUACACUCAAGCAAUCCUGAGGAAUACUGAGGGAGGGCCUGGCUACUGUCUCUCUGCACUCUGCUGCUUUGAAAUCUGGUUGAAAUGAGAAAAAGCAUUUUCUGUUUUCCCACCAGGCCCCCAAGUGUGGUCUUUUUCUUUCCUCCUAAUGUUGAAGAGAAAAAAAAAAAAAAAAGUUUGCCCAGAUUGCUUAAUUAAAAAUUGCAAACAAAAUCUCAUUUGAAGUCAGCACUUUGGUCAUUAUUAUCUCUGCUCACUGUAUUAUACUUUACAAAAAUGCAAGUCAUAGAAUAAGCAAAAGCAGUUAUUUUUGUUUACAUAGUAGGCUAUAAAUGCUUUUUUUUUCCUCUCAGAGUAAAAAACAUAACACAAUGCA